GAGCGCCCGGCCCCGGCGCCUGACUGUCCUCUGCCACUGCGGAGAGAGACGCUCCCAUGGAUCCACGUGUUUCCCCCGUCGUCCCCGCACUCCUUUUAAGUCGCCUGGAAUUUAGAACGAACACGUUUCUCCUCUGGCCCUCCAGUCUCUGGGGAAGCAAAAAUUAACGAGAUGCUUGCACAUACCACCCAGGUGUUCCGGUCUUUCACGAUGCAUUAAAGGGUUGGUCUUGCUGUAAGAGAAGAACAACUGAUUUUUCUGAUUUCUUAAGCAUUGUAGGCUGUACAAAAGGUAGACAUAAUAGUGAGAAGCCACCUGAGCCAGUCAAACCUGAAGUCAAGACUACUGAGAAGAAGGAGCUAUGUGAAUUAAAACCCAAAUUUCAGGAACACAUCAUUCAAGCCCCUAAGCCAGUAGAAGCAAUAAAAAGACCAAGCCCAGAUGAACCAAUGACAAAUUUGGAAUUAAAAAUAUCUGCCUCCCUAAAACAAGCACUUGAUAAACUUAAACUGUCAUCAGGGAAUGAAGAAAAUAAGAAAGAAGAAGACAAUGAUGAAAUUAAGAUUGGGACCUCAUGUAAGAAUGGAGGGUGUUCAAAGACAUACCAGGGUCUAGAGAGUCUAGAAGAAGUCUGUGUAUAUCAUUCUGGAGUACCUAUUUUCCAUGAGGGGAUGAAAUACUGGAGCUGUUGUAGAAGAAAAACUUCUGAUUUUAAUACAUUCUUAGCCCAAGAGGGCUGUACAAAAGGGAAACACAUGUGGACUAAAAAAGAUGCUGGGAAAAAAGUUGUUCCAUGUAGACAUGACUGGCAUCAGACUGGAGGUGAAGUUACCAUUUCAGUAUAUGCUAAAAACUCACUUCCAGAACUUAGCCGAGUAGAAGCAAAUAGCACAUUGUUAAAUGUGCAUAUUGUAUUUGAAGGAGAGAAGGAAUUUGAUCAAAAUGUGAAAUUAUGGGGUGUGAUUGAUGUAAAGCGAAGUUAUGUAACUAUGACUGCAACAAAGAUUGAAAUCACUAUGAGAAAAGCUGAACCGAUGCAGUGGGCAAGCCUUGAACUGCCUGCAGCUAAAAAGCAGGAAAAACAAAAAGAUGCCACAACAGAUUGAGUGGGAGAUGGAAGGAAGGCUAUUACAUUAUUUCCGAAUUUUUAAUACUGUGUGAAGUGGUGGCUUGCUGCUGUAAUCUUUUGUUUUGUUGUUGUGUUACUGAAUGUGGCAUUUCAGGGUUAACAUUAGGUUCUUAAAAGCCAAAGUCAGUUUGUCUUUUUGUGCCUCUCAUCUUUCUUUUGUGUUAUGUAAGAUUGAUUAUUCAUUUCUCCCUACUGGUAGGAACCAUAGUUGUGUCCUAUACUUGAAGAGGCUGGAAAGUAGCCCAUAACCAUAAUUGCAGUAUUUCUUUGUAUUUCUCUGUUAAGCAAAGAAAUAUUAAGGAACAUUUUUUUUAUGUUUUUGUAUUAUUCCAUAAUUAGUAAAGCAAGAUGAAAUGUCAAAUUUUAAUCAGUUUUUUCAUGGAUUUGUGUUCUUACAGUACUUGAAAAUAUUUAAGGAAGAGAUGAAGCUCUGCAGUUUUUUCUAUGUGGGAUGAUUACUUUUUUAAGGAGGAUUAAUUCUGAGGUAGUAUAGUAACUAAAGGGGAAUAUAUGAAUUGUUUAACAAAUUAGAAUUUGUUUACAACUACUUGAAUUUUUAAAUUAUGUCAAAACUUACAUUACUUGCCAAGCAGUAUGAUGUUAUAGGAAACAUAAAUAAGAUUACAGAGGUAUCAAUUUGGUUAAAAUUCACCAUUUUAUAAGACUAAGCAAUAAUCUUAACAACCUCUUUCCUGAAUAUUUAAAUGUGUUUGUAUGGUGUUAUGACUAAUUGUUACUGAUUUAGAGACUAAGCCCUCUUAAAACCUUUAGUUAAAUAUAAAAAGAAAUUAUAUAUAUCUUGCCUCCCUGAUGGAAAACUAUAUAAAAUUGUAGACUUAAAAGGUUUGUGGAAAUACAUUAGGAUAUCAGAAAACUAAAUAUAUGGAGUUGCUUUAUGACUAUUACAUGUUAAAUAAAAAUAGCUUAAUUGUUUUGGAGUUUUUUUUUAAAGUCAUGAAGAGCUUCACAAUUCUAGUGAUACAAUGUUGACUAUAUAUUGUACUUUAUAUUAAAUAUAGGUAAUACAGAAUUAGAUCGUUUGGAUAGGUUUUGAGUUAGUGCAGAACUCAAGAAGAAAAAUUAGGAAAUAUUCUGAAGGCCAGAACUCUGGAAGAACUUAGAAAGUUUGGGAAUAAAUUAAACUUAUGUAGAUUUAAAAUUAAAAGGGGUUUAUUUCCCAAACCCCUUGAGUCUUUUCUUUUCCUUGGUAUUUAUGGAAUUCUUACAAAGAAAAAUUUGCAGAAGUACUAUUUUCGUGAAUAAAACAUAUGUAUCAUUCUACUACCAUUAGCAAAUAACUUAGUUGUAGUUAAUAUAAUUGUUAAAAGGUUUAGCUCUGUUACAAAUAAAAACAUAAAGAUCUGGCAACCAGACUUUCAUGAUGUUACAUUACCAUGACAAGAAACUCUGGGCAGUAAAAGUUGGACCCACAUGGAGUACAUAAGCAUCUGAUACCUGGAGAUGUAUUUAAAAUUUUUCAAGUUAUCUUCCAUGAUUUAGGAACCAUUUAGAGACAUGAAGUCUUUAUGGGUUGGGGGAAAGGUUGAUAAUUAGUUUGAUUAAAGGUAAUGAUUAAUAUCCCUUUUUGUUCAUACUUCCUUCUGAGGCUGUUUUCCCCUAAACAGUAUCUUAAUCUGUUACAUGUAAUUGAAAUAUUAUUUGAAGCAGUGAGUUAUUGUAACCUCAGAUUAGUUACAUUGAUCAAAACAUUGAUUUAUACACACACACACACACAUACAUAUGUAGCUUUUAUAUUUAGUCUGGUUACAUUAGUGACCAUGGUAUUUACUUUCUUCUUAAGGAGCCUUUGAAUUUCUUGUCCAGAUAAAAAUCCGAAUAUUUCUCUUAGACUCAUACAUAAAGGGACACAGUUAUCGUUAGGUAGCAUAUGUUUUACUAUCGGUUUGUCAAAAAAGUUAAUAAAAAGUGCUUAUUGAUUUAUUUCUCUAGAAA